CUCUUCUCCCCUCCCCCAAGCCAGCACCUGGUGCCCCGGCGGGUCGUGCGGCGCGGCGCUCCGCGGUGAGCGCCUGACCCCGAGGGGGCCCGGGGCCGCGUCCCUGGGCCCUCCCCACCCUUGCGGUGGCCUCGCGGGUCCCAGGGGCGGGGCUGGAGCGGCAGCAGGGCCGGGGAGAUGGGCGGUGGGGAGCGCGGGAGGGACCGGGCCGAGCCGGGGGAAGGGCUCCGGUGACUUAAGGGGAGGGAAUGCUCCUCUGCCGUGCUCACCGCGUGCUGGGGCUGCGCGGGGCUAGGUAUGGUCGGGCUGUUUUCCCACUGUCCCUUCUUCGGGCAGUGUCGCCGUCCAGCCUGGUUGUUGAAGCGUCCCCGUGGUCCCCCGGGGUCCAGGCCCCUUUGUGGAGGCAGCUGCUGGCCCCCAGCCCAUGGGACCGUAGUCGCGGAGGCCUCUGCAGAGGCGCAGGCUGGAAGCGGUGGCCUUUGAGGGGGGCGGCAGGAGAGAGUACCGACCUCCCUCGAACUCCUGGCAGAGGUGGGGGUCGCAGCAAAAGCACUGGGGUGGAGGGCGGCCAGUGUGGGGCAGACGCCUGUGUGCCUUCCUCAGAUACGGGCAGAGUUGUGGAUGUGAGAAGGGUCUGGCUUGGGUACCUCAGUUCCAAACCUCCUGUGUCCAUCAGAGAGCUGGCGGUCACCAUGGCAAUGCGGGAGCUGGUGGAGGCCGAAUGCGGGGGUGCCAACCCGCUCAUGAAGCUCGCCGGGCACUUCACCCAGGACAAGGCCCUUCGGCAGGAGGGAUUGAGGCCUGGCCCCUGGCCCCCCGGAGCCCCGGCCUCUGAGGCAGCCUCCAAGCCUUUGGGAGUAGCUUCUGAAGAUGAGUUGGUGGCUGAAUUCCUGCAGGACCAGAAUGCACCCCUUGUGUCCCGUGCCCCUCAGACCUUCAAGAUGGAUGACCUCCUGGCUGAGAUGCAGCAGAUUGAGCAGUCAAACUUCCGCCAGGCUCCCCAGAGAGCCCCUGGUGUGGCAGACUUGGCCUUGUCUGAGAACUGGGCCCAGGAGUUUCUUGCAGCUGGAGAUGCUGUGGAUGUAACUCAGGAUUAUAAUGAGACUGACUGGUCCCAAGAAUUCAUCUCUGAAGUUACAGACCCCUUGUCUGUGUCCCCUGCCCGCUGGGCUGAGGAAUAUUUGGAGCAAUCAGAGGAGAAGCUGUGGCUGGGAGAACCUGAGGGAACAGCCACCGAUCGCUGGUAUGAUGAAUAUCAUCCUGAGGAGGAUCUGCAGCACACGGCCAGUGACUUUGUGGCCAAAGUGGAUGACCCCAAAUUGGCUAAUUCUGAGUUCCUGAAAUUCGUGCGGCAGAUUGGCGAAGGGCAGGUGUCCCUGGAGUCCGGUGCAGGGUCGGGCCGAGCUCAGGCAGAACAGUGGGCAGCAGAGUUUAUACAGCAGCAGGGUACAUCAGAUGCCUGGGUUGACCAGUUCACAAGACCAGUAAACACAUCUGCCCUUGAUAUGGAGUUUGAACGAGCCAAGUCAGCUAUAGAGUCUGAUGUCGAUUUCUGGGACAAGUUGCAGGCAGAGUUGGAGGAGAUGGCAAAACGGGAUGCUGAGGCCCACCCCUGGCUUUCUGACUAUGAUGACCUUACGUCAGCUACCUAUGAUAAGGGGUACCAGUUUGAGGAGGAGAACCCCUUGCGUGAUCACCCUCAGCCUUUUGAAGAAGGGCUGCGGCGCCUUCAGGAGGGGGACCUGCCAAAUGCUGUGCUGCUUUUUGAGGCAGCUGUGCAGCAGGAUCCUAAGCACAUGGAAGCUUGGCAGUAUCUGGGUACCACCCAGGCAGAGAAUGAACAAGAACUAUUAGCCAUCAGUGCAUUGCGGAGGUGUCUGGAGCUAAAGCCAGAUAACCAGACAGCACUGAUGGCGCUGGCUGUGAGCUUCACCAACGAGUCCCUGCAGCGACAGGCCUGUGAAACCCUACGAGACUGGCUGCGGUACACACCAGCCUAUGCCCAUCUGGUGACACCUGCUGAAGAAGGGGCUGGUGGGGCAGGACUGGGCCCCAGCAAGCGUAUCCUGGGAUCUCUCUUGUCUGACUCCCUGUUUCUUGAAGUGAAAGAGCUCUUCCUGGCAGCUGUGCGGCUGGACCCUACCUCCAUUGACCCUGAUGUGCAGUGUGGCUUGGGAGUCCUUUUCAACCUGAGUGGGGAGUAUGACAAGGCCGUGGACUGCUUCACAGCUGCCCUCAGCGUUCGUCCCAAUGACUAUUUGCUGUGGAAUAAGCUAGGCGCCACCCUGGCCAAUGGAAACCAGAGUGAAGAAGCAGUAGCUGCGUACCGCCGGGCCCUCGAGCUCCAGCCUGGCUAUAUCCGGUCCCGCUAUAACCUGGGCAUCAGCUGCAUCAACCUCGGGGCUCACCGGGAGGCUGUGGAGCACUUUCUGGAGGCCCUGAACAUGCAGAGGAAAAGCCGGGGCCCCCGGGGUGAAGGAGGUGCCAUGUCGGAGAACAUCUGGAGCACCCUGCGUUUGGCAUUGUCUAUGUUAGGCCAGAGCGAUGCCUAUGGGGCAGCCGACGCGCGGGAUCUGUCCACCCUCCUAACUAUGUUUGGCCUGCCCCAGUGACAGUGGGACGGGCUGCCCUGUGAGUGUCCACCUGGAGGGAUCCCCGCUUUGGAUGUGAUUCCCUCUCCCCAAAUGGGCCUACCAAGGGGGCGGGCUGAUGACCAUAAGCGGUACGGCCUUUCAGGAGCUGCCUCAACGUAGGGGUGGGUAGUCUGUGUUCUAGUUCCUACAUAAUUGUAGGAAAAUGAGCUGUGUCAUCUCUGAGUCCCUUGGUAAUUCAAGGGCUGUACAUCCAGCUACAGAUCUCUCUGCUCAUCAUGCCCUUUCUUGGUGCUGCUUUUUGGGUAGGACCCCACGAUUUAGGGUAACUGUUAUCAUCAGCUGCCAUUUCUGAUAGGGUCUACCACAUCUGUAAUGUCUGUCCUUUCCCCCACUUUUACUGGGAAUUGAUAGUCCAGCUUCCUUGGGCAGUGUAAGUAGGAGGUUCAUCUGCUGUGCGCCUCUAAUGUCUGUCUGGAUGGGAUGUGUUAGGAGUUGGCCUGUUGGGUUGAAUUGUUGAUUUGGCUGAGCAGAGCUGAGUUUUGGUAGGAGUGCUCAUGGUUCUGUCAUUCUUGGACCUCUCCUGGCUGAGCUCUGAUUCCCUGUGAGCACGAUGCUGAUGCAAUAGUCCUGUGUCAUCACUGCAGCGGUCCUCAGGAGCUGCCAGGGCCAAUUGCUACAGAGUGUCUGGGUGUGUGGCAUAGGAGGAAGGUUUGCUUGUGAAAUGAGGCUGGGUGGGAGCGGGGAGGGACUAGAUCAGAAGAGAUCAAGGGCUCUAUUCAGGAACGUUGGUGGGAGGACAGAGCAAGUGGGAAGGGGGUAUGGUGAGUGCGGCAAUCCCUCAUCCUCUUAGAAGCACCUGUGAAUGGGAAUUGAGCCAACUGUUAUAGAAAAUUGGUUCAGAAAGUGCAAUCUUGCCAGAUUUCUAGCAAAUAGGUUCAGUGUUACCAUAAGCCUUUGCUGUACUUCUUGAAAUGUUUCUAGGGGAGAGCAUUGGAAAAUCCCCUUCCCCCAUCUAGAUCGAAGGAAGAUGAGGGAGCAGCUUGGAUUCUUCUCAGUUGUCCCCUGCAUGGGGAGAUACACUAACCCCCAGAAAUGACUGCUAAGCCUCUUGCCUUGUCUUUAGUAGCUAAUGAUCAGAGAGAUUUUUUUUUUAAACUACCAUGGUCCCAGGAUUCCAUCCUGAAAUUUAUUUUUCUUUGUAUGAAUAUGUGUAAAUGAUUUAAAAAUAAAACUGUAAAAUAUUUGUACGAAGAA